AUGGAGCACAGCGGAGGGAAGGGAGACUGGCCUUGGGGAGUCCAGGCAGCUGCAGGGCCUUGGGGAGCAGCCCCCGUGACCAUGAGAGAGAAGUGGAGUGUGUGUGCCAAGCCAGCAACCCUGAGGCGGCCAGUGCUGGAGAUAGUGGUGAUAAUUCUUAGCAAGGACAGUGCUGCUGCUGACAGCCAUGCCCACCAGCCAGCAUACUCUGCAACAGUCCGAGUGACAGACGGGCCGCUCAGAAGAAAAGGCUUAUUCAUCAAUCUUCCAGGCAAUCUCUGGAAGAUGUUAUUCGGGCUGGAAACCAUGCUCUCACCCCACGUGGUGCAUGGGCUCCACCUGAGCACCCAGAGGGUCACAGGACACCCCUACUGGCUUGGAGGGUCACAGGACACCCCUACUGACCCAGAUUCAGAGGACAUCCCUACUUCCAGACCACCUAAGUUCUGCUUUCUGAUUUCUGGACAUGGGGUAAGAAUGACGGACCCCAAAAUGAUUGACGCUGGGCCUGCAUUUGAGGAGGGAGCAGGACCCAAGGAUGUCCUGUGGGCCCUGGGGACCAGGGAAGAAGAAUGUUGUCCCUUCCAGGUCGCCUGCAGUCCUUGCAGCUUCCUCUGUGGGAACACAAUUGAAAAGGCAGGGAAACCCUUGCUUCAUCAGGGCAGUGUUUGGGUCCAGAGUGAAGCCACCCUCUUCCAGCUCUCAAGGCUCCAUCGGGGACCCUCUUCCGGCUCUCAAGGCUGCAUCGGGGACCCUCUUCCGGCUCUCAAGGCUGCAUCGGGGACCCUCUUCCGGCUCUCAAGGCUGCAUCGGGGACCCUCUUCCGGCUCUCAAGGCUCCAUCGGGGACCCUCUUCCGGCUCUCAAGGCUCCAUCGGGGACCCUCUUCCGGCUCUCAAGGCUCCAUCGGGGACCCUCUUCCCGCUCUCAAGGCUCCAUCGGGGACCCUCUUCCGGCUCUCAAGGCUCCAUCGGGGACCCUCUUCCGGCUCUCAAGGCUCCAUCGGGGAAGCUCUUCCCGCUCUCAAGGCUGCAUCGGGGACCCUCUUCCCGCUCUAAAAGCUCCAUCGGGGACCCUAUUCCUGCUCUCAAGGCUGCAUCGGGGACCCUCUUCCGGCUCUCAAGGCUCCAUCGGGGACCCUCUUCCCGCUCUCAAGGCUGCAUCGGGGACCCUCUUCCAGCUCUCAAGGCUCCACCGGGGACCCUCUUCCGGUUCUCAAGGCUCCAUCGGGGACCCUCUUCCGGCUCUCAAGGCUGCAUCAGGGAGAGCAGAACACACGUCCCAGGCUUCUGCUUGUUCCCGGCACGACCCCUGCCUCCCCCUCUCCCCUGUCAAAUGCCACCAUUAUCUAUUUGAGAACCAUCAGGAUCACUUCUCCUGUCCCUUGUCCUGUGUUAUAAGCCACCUCAGAAAGCUGUUGUAGCUUUCCAGGGCAUCUCUUUCCCCGUUAACUGUAAUCCCCCUUUCUGACGCAGGACGCAGGCUGGUUCCAUGGGCAUCCUUCAAGGGCAUGUGUAAUGUGCAGUUUUAACUCAGAGCCCUGCACUCAGACCAAGGACCUGGUCUAUAGUGGGUGUUCGGAGACUGCAGAGCACCACCAUAACCCAGAAGGCUACAACAACUGGAAGCAGAUUGGGAGUGAGGAGGAAGUGGGCAGAGGAUGUCUGGUGGCCUUGGUGACCAGCAGCUGAGGACCCAUUGAUACCCAGGUGGAGAGGGAGGUGCCGAUUCUCCUGAAUCACGAGAGCAAAGAAAUCACACGUUCUGAGGCCACGAGCUGUCUGCUUUCACCGCGCCUCCCCUCUCAUCAGUGUGGAAGAAAAUCACCAUAUGCGUGAAUGUGACAGCUGAGGCUCAUGAAGACCUGAGUCAGGAGAAACAGGAUAAUACAUAUUUCAAAUGUUCUCUUUCCUAAGCCCAUUCCAUGUGUAAAAUGUUUUAGAAAGAUUUCCAUCCCACAUAAUUAAUUUUUCUUAAGGCCUUGGUUUUUAAAGAGGUAAGCUUGCCAAAUUUGGGCAUUUCACUGACGGGGAAUAUAUCUAAUUCCCCGAAACCUAGGUAAAUUCUUUCCUAAAUGGUAUAUGAUCCAUUAAGGAGUUUCCCAACCGAGUUUAGGGAAUAGAUACAAACUACAAAGCAUACCAUUAAAGAGCAAUUAAAGCACUAGCUCUGCCACAACUAUCAGGAAUAACAGGAUAACUGAAGCAGAGGACCUCACGUGGGCUGGGACAGGUGGAAAAGAUUCCAAGACAGCGCUGCACAAUCGCAAGCUCAUUGCAGGCAGGGAGCUCCGCCUAGCCCUCUUUGCAUCUCCUCUGAAAUGCUUACCUUGCAGGAGGUACUCUGAAAAUGCUUCCUGACUGAUGUCUGUAGGGGUGAGAUUUGGUGGGAGAAUAAUACAGCUAAUUGUGUAUGUGCGAAAGGGUUUGGUGUGAAACAGAGUGACUUGAUCUAGAUGAAUGAAAAGCCGUGUGGGGGAAUUGUGAGACAUCCUUAUUGCUAUGUAGGCUGCAGCAGAGGAUUGAAACAGCUGGUGGAUAGGGCAGCGCUCCAGGAUGUUGGCGUCCACGUGAGUUCCUGAGCUGAAGUCUGCAGAGCACCACCAUGACCCGGAAGGCAUACAGAACUUGGAGUGGAGGGAUCAGGAUUCAGAGCACGUUUCAGCGCUACACCGUAGGUGUAUUGCCUGGCUUCUCUGUCCCACCAUUUUAUCUUCCAUAAGCAGUUAUUAUUUACUUCUCGGGGACACAGCAAUAAGAUCACCACUCCUUGUCAACAUCGCAGAGGUGUGCGAGAGUGUGUAUGCACAGACAUGUGCACCUACUGUGUACCAUGCAUGAUCUUAAGCUGGUGAGUAAAGCAUGUCAUAAUAGUGGCGUAUUUUGAAAGGUUUUUCUGGCUGCAGAAUGACAAGGCAUGUAGGAAGGAAUGAGGAAGAAAAAAAUACUAAACUAAAAAGAAAUUCCCUUCAACAGCACUUUGUGUUGCCAAAUAUUUGGUUAUUUUACAGUUCUACCAAAAUGAGCCGUAGAAACAAAGUUCUAUUGAAAUGACAUCUAAAUAAUUUCUGAAGAUUUAUAGUUGCAGAAGAAGGUAUGUAAAUGUACACGUAAAAAAUGUGUAAUUAUUAGUAAGAAUCUGGCUUGGCCUAGCA